ACUCUGCAGUUGUCUCCCGAGCGCUGGCUGCGCCGCCCGAGCCGCUGGGCCGGGGAAGCACUGGCCGUUCGCUCCCGGGCCGGCUCCGCCAGGCGCUCGCAGGCAUGCAGCCCGGGAGCAGGAGGCGCUCCCCGGGCCGCUGCUGAGCCGGCCGGGGCGGCGGGGACCAGCGCCAGCGGAGCCCCUCCCACCUUGCCCCGGGGCAGACGAGCGGCGCCCCGACACCCCCUCUUCUCCCGCAGCCCCGCCAGCGCCACCCCCCGCGGGCCGCAGGGGCUCAUGCAGCCGCCAAGGGAGAGGCUAGUGGUAACAGGCCGAGCUGGAUGGAUGGGUAUGGGGAGAGGGGCAGGACGUUCAGCCCUGGGAUUCUGGCCGACCCUCGCCUUCCUUCUCUGCAGCUUCCCCGCAGCCACCUCCCCGUGCAAGAUCCUCAAGUGCAACUCUGAGUUCUGGAGCGCCACGUCGGGCAGCCACGCCCCAGCCUCAGACGACACCCCCGAGUUCUGUGCAGCCUUGCGCAGCUACGCCCUGUGCACGCGGCGGACGGCCCGCACCUGCCGGGGUGACCUGGCCUACCACUCGGCCGUCCAUGGCAUAGAGGACCUCAUGAGCCAGCACAACUGCUCCAAGGAUGGCCCCACCUCGCAGCCACGCCUGCGCACGCUCCCACCGGCCGGAGACAGCCAGGAGCGCUCGGACAGCCCCGAGAUCUGCCAUUACGAGAAGAGCUUUCACAAGCACUCGGCCACCCCCAACUACACGCACUGUGGCCUCUUCGGGGACCCACACCUCAGGACUUUCACCGACCGCUUCCAGACCUGCAAGGUGCAGGGCGCCUGGCCGCUCAUCGACAAUAAUUACCUGAACGUGCAGGUCACCAACACGCCUGUGCUGCCCGGCUCAGCGGCCACUGCCACCAGCAAGCUCACCAUCAUCUUCAAGAACUUCCAGGAGUGUGUGGACCAGAAGGUGUACCAGGCUGAGAUGGACGAGCUCCCGGCCGCCUUCGUGGAUGGCUCUAAGAACGGUGGGGACAAGCACGGGGCCAACAGCCUGAAGAUCACUGAGAAGGUGUCAGGCCAGCACGUGGAGAUCCAGGCCAAGUACAUCGGCACCACCAUCGUGGUGCGCCAGGUGGGCCGCUACCUGACCUUUGCCGUCCGCAUGCCAGAGGAAGUGGUCAAUGCUGUGGAGGACUGGGACAGCCAGGGUCUCUACCUCUGCCUGCGGGGCUGCCCCCUCAACCAGCAGAUCGACUUCCAGGCCUUCCACACCAAUGCUGAGGGCACCGGUGCCCGCAGGCUGGCAGCCGCCAGCCCUGCACCCACAGCCCCCGAGACCUUCCCAUACGAGACAGCCGUGGCCAAGUGCAAGGAGAAGCUGCCGGUGGAGGACCUGUACUACCAGGCCUGCGUCUUCGACCUCCUCACCACGGGCGACGUGAACUUCACACUGGCCGCCUACUACGCGUUGGAGGAUGUCAAGAUGCUCCACUCCAACAAAGACAAACUGCACCUGUAUGAGAGGACUCGGGACCUGCCAGGCAGGGCGGCUGCGGGGCUGCCCCUGGCCCCCCGGCCCCUCCUGGGCGCCCUCGUCCCGCUCCUGGCCCUGCUCCCUGUGUUCUGCUAGACGCGUAGAUGUGGAGGGAGGCGCGGGCUCCGUCCUCUCGGCUUCCCCAUGUGUGGGCUGGGACCGCCCACGGGGUGCAGAUCUCCUGGCGUGUCCACCAUGGCCCCGCAGAACGCCAGGGACCGCCUGCUGCCAAGGGCUCAGGCACGGACCCCUCCCCUUCUAGUGCACGUGACAAGGUUGUGGUGACUGGUGCCAUGAUGUUUGACAGUAGAGCUGUGUGAGAGGGAGAGCAGCUCCCCUCGCCCCGCCCCUGCAGUGUGAAUGUGUGAAACAUCCCCUCAGGCUGAAGCCCCCCACCCCCACCAGAGACACACUGGGAACCGUCAGAGUCAGCUCCUUCCCCCUCGCAAUGCACUGAAAGGCCCGGCCGACUGCUGCUCGCCGAUCCGUGGGGCCCCCUGUGCCCGCCACACGCACGCACACACUCUUACACGAGAGCACACUCGAUCCCCCUAGGCCAGCGGGGACACCCCAGCCACACAGGGAGGCAUCCUUGGGGCUUGGCCCCAGGCAGGGCAACCCCGGGGCGCUGCUUGGCACCUUAGCAGACUGCUGGAACCUUUUGGCCAGUAGGUCGUGCCCGCCUGGUGCCUUCUGGCCUGUGGCCUCCCUGCCCAUGUUCACCUGGCUGCUGUGGGUACCAGUGCAGGUCCCGGUUUUCAGGCACCUGCUCAGCUGCCCGUCUCUGGCCUGGGCCCCUGCCCCUUCCACCCUGUGCUUAGAAAGUCGAAGUGCUUGGUUCUAAAUGUCUAAACAGAGAAGAGAUCCUUGACUUCUGUUCCUCUCUCUCCUGCAGAUGCAAGAGCUCCUGGGCAGGGGUGCCUGGGCCCCAGGGUGUGGCAGGAGACCCAGUGGAUGGGGCCAGCUGGCCUGCCCUGAUCCUCUGCUUCCUCCUCACAACCCCAAGAGCCCCCAGCCCGGUCCAUCCACGUCUGGAGUCUGGGGAGAGGAGCAGGGUCUUAGGACUCUCAGCUCUGAGCAUCCCUGGCAGGGUCUUCAACCUCUAAUCUCUUCCCUUAAGCCCUGUGGCCACACAGCCAGGAGAGACUUGCCGCUGGCUCCCGCCUCAUUUCAGCCCAGGGUGCUCAUCCAGGGGCCCAGAACAGUCCCACCUGUGCUGCUGUGCCCACAGCACAAAGCCAGGCUUCACUCCCAAAAGUGCAGCCAGGCCCUGGAGGGUGAUCCUGCCAGCAGCCCUACAGCUCCACACCCUACCCACCCAUCGGCAGCCCCUCUGCUGUUCCCCAGGGACCUCUCAUACACUGGCCAGGAGGCUGCAGAACGUGUGUCUCCCCCUCCCUCCAAGAGGUCCUGCUCCCUCUGCCAGAACCGUGUGUGGGCGGGUGGGAGGGCGCUCGGGGCCCGGCCCCUCCCUCUCCCUGCUGGUUUUAGUUGGUCCCUAUGUUGGAAGUAAAAAGUGAAGCACUUUAUUUUGGUUGUGUUUGCUCACGUUCUGCUUGGAAGUGGGGACCCCUCACUGCGUCCACGUGUCUGCGACCUGUGUGGAGUGUCACCGCGUGUACAUACUGUAAAUUAUUUAUUAAUGGCUAAAUGCAAGUAAAGUUUGGUUUUUUUGUUAUUUUCUUUUAGACGUGUUGGAGUUUGUUUUCUGAACAGACUUUGGCUCCCUUGAGGCGGGUGGAGGAUGGACUUUGGUGGUGGGAUCCCCUGCAGCAAGUGUGUGUGUGUGCGCGCAUGUGUGUGUGCGCGCAUGUGUGUAUGCAUGCCUGUGUGUGUGCGUGCCUGUGUGCGUGCAUGUACGCAUGUGUGCGCAUGCCUGUGUGUGCGCCCAUGCCUAUGUGUGUGCAUGUAGGCAUGUGUGUGCGCAUGUGUAUGUGCGUGAGAAUGGUGUGAAGGCGGAUAGAAGAUGCAGCAGUUUAACAGCCACCACACAUUGCUUUUGUAAAGUCACUUUUCCUCCUCACGAUGAGCUGUCUUUGGAGCUUGGCAGGCCCAGAUCCUCUUGUUCUAGUGACAGUGGAACACAGUCAGGGAGACAGGUGACUAUGUGGUGGAGAGACAUAUGGUGCCCUCUGGGAUGAGAUGGGUGGGAUAGCCUGAGAUCUGGGAUGACUCCCUCUCAGCCACUGCUAUCAGCCUGGAGCCCCAGCUGUUGGGACUGCCUGCCACCCUCCCUGCCAGUGCCCAUCUUCUCAUAGCCCGGGCGGAGCAGUGGUGCUGCAGGAGGCUGCUGUCCACGUCACUGUGGGACCAGGUUUAUUGGCAGCUGUGAUCACAUUUCAUCUGUACAAACUACCCAGUGAAUCAGGAAGAAAUUCAGGCCCAUUUUGCCGAUGAAACAGACUCUGAGAUUAACUGACUUGCCUAGGGCUCCUUAGCAACGGGAAGGACAACCUGUGCACCUAGGUUAGUAUUGUCCUGAAGCCCCUUCUCUUCAAACUAAAUGCCAUGAGGCAGAAUAGCAGCACAGUUAAGCCAGCCUACAUCCUGGCUUCUCCACCUCCCCAGCAGUGUGACCAUGGGCAAGUCACUUCACCUCUCUGAGCCUGCAUGCUGUUCUCUGGAAGAUGGGGGGGUGCCUGUCCCAUACAGUUGUUUGGAGAGUCAGGAGUUCAUUCCUGUAAAUUGCUUAGGAGAGGGCGGGGCACACAUGGCUUGUCUGGUCGUGGGGAGGGAGGGGGUGGUAUUAUCCCAAAGCAAGAUAAAUCAGUUAAGGGGAGAAGGAAAGGGGCGAUACAGACCCUGGACUCUUGGGAGAGGUGAACCUGCAGGCUAGCAAGGGGAGGAGUCCCAAGAGUGGCCAAGUUCAUUAAUCCCAGGCAGACCAGGAAGGCUGAAGAAAAAGGAGAACUUUAUUUUAUUUUUGAAAUGGAGUCUGGCGUCUUGCUCUGUCGCCAGGCUGGAGUGCAGUGGCACCAUCCCAGCUCACUGCAGCCCCUGCCUCCCAGGUUCAAGCAAUUCUCCUGCCUCAGCCUCCCAAGUAGCUGGGACUACAGGCACACACCACCACGCCUGGCUAAUUUUUUGUAUUUUAGUAGAGAUGGUGUUUCACCAUGUUGACCAGUAUGGUCUUGAUCUCCUGACCUCGUGAUCCGCCUGCCUUGGCCUCCCAAAGUGUUGGGAUUACAGGCGUGAGCCACCACCGUGCCCGGCCAAAAAAGGAGAACGUUCUAAAGCCCUGUUCUUGCAGGGCUCCCAGAGAGAACACGGGAGUUGGGUUUGGGAGGCAGGAACCAGACUGGAAAGGACAAAACGUACCCAGCAUCUUCCCUGGCGGCCGGAACCGUCACUACAGGCCCCGUGCCCUUAGCAGUCCCAGGGACAGAGCGACUCAGGGAGGCAGCAAGGAGGAGCGGAGCCAUUGGUGCUCGUCCGGCACAGAGAACAGUUCCUGAGAAGCCAGGGCACACAGAAGAAAAAGAAAAAAGAAAUCUCUACUAGACGAAAAUGCUAAAUGGCACUAGCCACAAAGUAUUCUUGGUUUGGAAUUUUUUUUCCAGGACCCUAAAUGUAACCGGCUGGAAUUCUUUCCCAAGUGCCAUGCUACUUACUACUGGUUGCCCUCACGAGCAUGGAAAUGCCGUCGUGAAUAUGGAACACAGCAUCCUGAGCUAAAAGAUUCCCAAGAAGCAGCUUCAUCUUGCAGGACGGGCUAGGUUGGGAGCCUCUGGAGGUUCCUGGCUGCCAGCUCCGCGGAGGCCUGCGGCCUGGAGGUAAAUGCAUUAGCACACGGAGGUGGGCGCCUCUCCCCGCCCCAUCCUGUCUCACUGAUGUGUUGCCGAGAACUGGAGUUCUUGUUUAGCUAACCAGAAUGUGCAAGGCUAUAGGACAGGAGAGAAAUGGCCUUUAAAACAAAUGAAUGAGAGUCACGAUGAAGGGGGCAGACGGGGGGGUGAAAAUCAUUACCAGAACACUUGGGCAGAGACCCGUCAGAGCCAGGCAGGAGACAGUCAUCAGAGCUGUGCCAGCAAGUGGCAUGGAGCAGGGGUGGCACUUGGGCUCGGGCUGCAGGCAAACUUGGCGUCAAAACUGGCUCAACCCGUCGCGAGCUGUGUGGUCUCCUUGGGAUUUUUUGAGCCUUAGAUUCCUUAUUUGUAAAAUGGAUUUGUGAGUCUCCACCUCCCGAGGUCAGUAUGGAAAUCCAGUGAGCUAACACUCGUCAAUGGCCUCGCACAUGGCCCUGGCACCACGCAUGGAGGCCGCCAAAAGUGGCCGCCUCCUCUCUGCAAUUGCAUUUAUUUAUCCAUUUGAUAACUCUAUUGGGUGUCUACCCAGCAUUGUUCAGGGGGGUGUGAGGGGCUACCGCAAUGACCCAGACAGACUGCUGUGCAUUCUUAUUGGAAAGACAAGGCAAUAAACCACAGUUACAAAACCCAGGGUCCCAUGGUAACGAGCUCCACAGAGAAAAGGGAAGUGGGCCAGAGGUUCCGAGAGACACACAUUUUGGAUUGCAGGAGGGUGAGAAGGGGCAUUCAUCUGUGGUGGGGUUAAGGGGAGGCCUCCGACUAGCUCACCUGCAUGAAUUUCAGGAACAAGCCAUGCAGAGCCGGACAGAGCAUUCUGUGCAGAGAAAACAGUGUAACAGCCCUAGAGCAGCAGCAGCAAAGGGGGAGUUUAAGGGAUGGUGGGAAGCCACUGUCACUGGACAGUAGCAAGUGGACAGACCAGGGGUCCCAGGUGAGGCCACAGAGCAGCCAAAGUACUGCAGGGCUCUCCGGCUCCGGGAGGACUUGAUGUUUGACUCCAGUUGCCAGAGGAAGCCGUUCACGGGCUUUGAGUGUAGGAAUGAUGUGUCCGACUUGGGUCUUUUUAUUGUUCUUUUUUAGAGACAGGGUCUCACUCUGUCACCCAGGCUGGAGUGCAGCGGCACAAUCACAGCUCACUGCAGCCUCCACUUCCUGGGCUCAAGCAAUCCUCCCACUUCAGCCACUCAAGUAGCUGGGAUUACAGGUGCCUGCCGUCACACCCGGCUAAUUGUUAAAUUUUUUUGGAGAGACAGGAUCUUGCUGUUUUCCCAGGCUGAUCUUGAACUCCUGGGCUCAAGCGAGACGUCUGUUUCAGCCUCCCAAAGUGCUGGGAUAACAGGUGUGAGCCACUGGGCCUGCCUUGGCUUGGGUAUUAAAGGAAUUGUUCUAGUUACUAUAUGGAGGUGACUUGGGGCCGCUGGGGAAGAAAGAGGAAGUCAGGAGCCAGUCUGAGGCAGUGGCAAUGCAGCGAUUAUCAGAAAUAAUGGGCUCAAUGAUAGACUGGAUAAAGAAAAUGUGGCACAUAUACGCCAUGGAGUACUAUGCAGCCAUAAAAAGGGAUGAGUUCAUGUCCUUUGCAGGGACAUGGAUGAAGCUGGAAACCAUCAUUCUCAGCAAACUAACACAAGAACAGAAAACCAAACACCGCAUGUUCUCACUCGUAAGUGGGAGUUGAACAAUGAGAACACAUGGACACAGGGAAGGGAACAUCACACACUGGGGCCUGUCAGUGGGUGGGGGGCUGGGGGAGGGAGAGCAUCAGGAGAAAUACCCAAUGUAGAUGAUGACGGGUUCAUAGGUGCAGCAAACCACCAUGGCACGUGUAUACCUAUGUAACAAACUUGUGCGUUCUGCACGUGUACCCCAUAACUGAAAGUAUAAUCAUAAUUUUAAGAAAAGAAAUGAUGGCCUUUGGGGUCUAAUAAGAAGGUGGGGCUGACAGGGCUUGGGGAGAGAGCGAGCUUGACAGGAGACCACGAUGUCUUCCCCAGGGGUCUGAGCACCUGGGGAAAUGGUGGUGCCAUUUACCAUGACUGGAAAGAUCAUGGGAGGAGCAGGUUUGGGACACUGAAGGCCCGAGAGCCCCUGGCAAACCACCAGUGUAAGUCCAAGAGUCCAAAAGCUGAAGAACUUGGAGUCCAAUGUUUGAGGGUAAAAAACAGCCAGCAUGAGAAAAAGAUGAAGGCCAGAAGACUCGUCCAGUCUAGCCCUUCCACAUUCCUCUGCCCGCUUUUAUCCUAGCCUCGCUGGCAGGUGAUUAGAUGGUGCCCACCCAGGUUAAGCGUGGGUCUCUGUCUCCCAGUUCACUGACUCAAAUGUUAAUUUCCUUUGGCGACAGCCUCACAGACACACCCAGGAACGAUACUUUGCAUCCUCCAAUCCAAUCAAGUUGGCACUCAAUAUUAAACAGUUUCGGCCGGGAGCGGUGGCUCACGCCUGUAAUCCCAGCACUUUGGGAGGCCAAAGCGGGCAGAUCACUAAGUCAGGAGAUCGAGACCAUCCUGGCUAACACGGUGAAACCCCAUCUCUACUAAAAAUACAAAAAAUUAGCCAGGCGUGGUGGUGGGCGCCUGUAGUCCCAGCUACUCGGGAGGCUGAGGCAAGAGAGUGGCGUGAACCCGGGAGGCAGAACUUGCAGCAAGCAGAGAUCGCACCACUGCACUCCAGCCUCCAGCCUGGGCGACAGAGCAAGACACCGUCUCAAAAAAAAAAAAAAAACAACUAACAGUUUCGUUCAUUAAGGCAAUGUCCAUGGGGCAGCUCCUGCAUGCCACGCCACCCCUGCCCUGACAUACUCCCAGGCUGACCAGCCAGAACUGGGGAGAGGGCAUCUUGAAGAAACAGUCCACCCUCCGCCCUCGCAUACCUGUGUCUCCCAGCAGACAAGACACACAAGGGCAGGGACUGCACUUUCCUGUGUGCAAAUCUCAGGUAUGGUCCAGAAAUCACAUCUCUUUGGUCUGAUUGGCCUUACUUACCAAACCCUUGAAACAAUGGAAAGAAGCUUGCUGCAAUGGGAAGACCCCUGCCCCCCAAACCCUCUAACCAGGAGUCUACAGACCUCAUUCCGUGGAAGUUCCCAUUGUCCCCUGGGAAACCACCACCUUCUGAAUCGGCACAGCCAAGGCCCCCAACCCUGCUAUCAACAGCUUUCCUUAGCCACCUUCCCCAUCCUGCAGGGCUUUUCAACAUUUCGACUUUUUAAUCCUUCCCUCCCUAAGAUAUAGACAUGGUGUUAGUAGCAGAACCCUGAAGGCAAAGGAACAGAAACUAACACUCUCAGAAAGUCCUAGCAGGAUGGUCUGAAUUAAUAGACAGCUGCAGGCAGCCAGUGUGCAAGGCACGCUCGUAAUGUCAGUGGCGUUCCGGAAUGAGGGCUGUGAUCCCAGGCAGCCCAGAUCCCAAGGCGAAAACAUUCAUGUCGCCCAGCAUCACCCUGUCCUUGCCCAGGGUGACCCUGAGACGGCACUUGGAUUCUUCCACAUCUGAACUCAAACCUGCUCCCUCAGCUCUCCCCAGCAGGAAUUGGAGCCCUCUCCAGGCCGUUCAGCCAAAGCAGAAUGUGUCUGGCCAAGCAGAUCUGCCCAGAGAAGAACAAAGACGUGUUCAGACACUGUCUGGGGAAUUGGUUUUGAGCUCACUCUGAGCUCCAUCUGUGCAACAAGGCCAGCGUCAGCUGUUACAGAGAAGGGGCUUGUGGCAGUUUAUUACCCUGGUGAGCUGGCUCGGGGCCAUGCUGACCGCAGGACUGUAAAGGACAUAAGGCAGUUGGCAAUAUGGGAAGCAGCAGUCCCCAAAGCACCCCGUCAAGGAAACGAUGCAAGAGCUCUGUCCACUGGACCAGCCCCACCCUACCCCGCCACGCCCUGGCCUAGGGGGAGGGACCUUGUGUUUCACGGGCCUGGAUGGCCAGGGAUGGACAGUGGCAUGGGCACAGACACACCCAGACCGAAGGAAGGGCCCGGGCUCCAGAACCAGACCCGAUCCAGGCUCCCAGCUCUGUCACCUACUGGCUGCAUGAAAAGGGUGGGUUUUCCUUGUUUUGCAGCCUCAGCUAUCUCAGCUGUGAGGGAACAAUGACGCCACCUCCCUCACGUGGCGGUCCUGAAGAUGAAAUGUAAUGCAUGCAGCGCGGCGGCCGGCCCACCGUGUGCUCUUAGUAACUGGCCGCUGUUCUCUUCAGCCCUCCCGUUACUGACCACCUCGAGGGCACCGUUCCUCCAAGCUGACCAUUUCCUGCCAGUCACCCACUGCCCAGCUCGCCCAGCCAUGGAGUGGGCUCUGGUCCACGUGCAUGGUGAGCUGCCAUCUUUGUCGUCCUCUGGACACCACGUCUACCUCCUUGGGAAAUAGAAACGAGUCCUGCAUUGCUUUGUCAAAUUUCACAAAAACCCUAGAAAGCAGAUAUUGCCCUGGUUUACAGACGGACAGACAGAAGCAAAGAGAAGCCAACUGACCCACUCCAGGUUACAAGCAGGGUCUGGUAGGAGAGCACGCGUCCACCCCACCGCUCACUGCGCCCACCUACUCCUCGCUUGAGGGCAGAGAACGAGCUGGGGCGGGGCGCUCCAGGGGGCACAGGCAGCCUGUGUUCAAGGCAUGCUCGUGAGCCCCACAGCAGGGGCGGAGUCAAACCAGGGCUCUGGUUCUGGGGUGAGCAGAGGGUGGGGCCAGGCCCCCACUGGGAGGCUGACUGAGGAGGGGCUCAAAGGGCAGGCAGGCUCCAUCAGAGCGGUUUGAUGAGCAGGGCCGCUGAGUGGCCCUCAGGUCAAGGCUGGGGCCGGGACCACCAGGGACCAGGUCUGCGGGGCCAGGGGUCCCUCCCCAGGGUGGAGCAGGAAAACUCCGGCAACCGCCUUCUUGAGUGGACUUGACCUUCCCUUUCUCUGCUAAUGAUCUCAGAUUAAUCCCUUAAGGCAAGUGCCCCAGGGUGGGUGUUGGUUGCAUAAAACAAGAGGAGUCCUUCUUCCCUUCCUUCCUGGCACAAACAUUUGUAGGCCACCCCCGAUGUGGCUGGUCGUAGUCUGGAUUUGGGGGCACAUUCAGGCAUUCAACAAAUACGUCAUGAGGCCCCGUGAUGAGCUGGGGGGCUAUGCUUGAUGUCGGCAGUACAGCUGUGGUCGCUCGAAUGAAUGUGCCCGCCCUCACGGGACUGACCUCUAGUGGUGAGAGACAGACACUAACCGAGUCACAUGUGUGAUUACACGUGUAAUCAUACUUACAUAUGUAACAACACGAGUUACACGUGCAGUGUGGGGAGGGGGCCCUUCACGGUGACCAGCCCAUCAGGGAAGGGGAUGCGGGUGGCAGAAGGAAGCGGCACACCCUUGUCCUCACGGAGCUCACAGGAGGUUCUCUGACCCUCAUCUUAAGCCACAGGCUGUGUCUGAGCCUCACUGCCCUAGCUAUCAACUGGGUGCAGGACUAGGCCUUAAUCACUGGGCAGCGGGAAGAACUACAUAAGCUCAUACUGGCGCAAAGCCCCUUGGGAGACCGCAGGGAAAGCCAUUGCAUGAGGUGGUGACAGGCUCGGCCUUCAGAGUCGGGCUAGAAUCUGAGUUCUGACAAUGAUCCCCGCCUUGACCCAUCUCUCCUCAGGCCGCCCUGAGCCUUCCAGUUAGGCCUGGGCUUUGGGCUUCCGUGUUUGUCUCUGGAUUGUUCGGUUUUAGCAAGAGUCCUGCUAAAUUGGUCUUGCUGGAAUCCUCCGCCCUCCACAUCUGAUUGCCCUUCCUGUCUGAUCGUGGUCUUCAUGCCCCACGGCCUCCAGGGGACGUCUGAUCACCUGGCCUGCCUUCAGCAAGAAUCCCCCCAGGUGUUUCCUCUUAAGAGGUUUUCCAUCCACUGAGCCCACCCUGCUCCUUGGCCAUCAAUUCCCACUUGCCUGUACUGUAUUCAGAGGGGACCCCAAUCUCUCUUCCCAGCUGCAGCGGUCCCUGUCCAACACUGCCCCCCACCUCAAAUAAAGUCUUUCUUACUGUCUUUAACAUAUGCCGUCAAUAAAGUUUUAGCAGAUCCAA